GGGGGUGAGGCGCUGAAAGCCCACGGUGGGCGCUGUGUCUCCGCAGGGGAGUGAAUGCCCAAACCAAGAACGGUGCCACGCCCCUGUACCUGGCGUGCCAGGAGGGCCACCUGGAGGUGACGCAGUACCUGGUGCAGGAAUGCGGCGCGGACCCGCACGCGCGCGCCCACGACGGCAUGACCCCACUGCACGCCGCGGCGCAGAUGGGCCACAGCCCGGUCAUCGUGUGGUUGGUGAGCUGCACCGACGUGAGCCUGUCGGAGCAGGACAAAGACGGCGCCACCGCCACGCACUUCGCGGCGAGCCGCGGCCACAGCAAGGUGCUCAGCUGGCUGCUGCUGCACGGCGGGGAGAUCUCGGCUGACCUGUGGGGCGGGACCGCGCUGUACGACGCCGCCGAGAACGGGGAGCUAGGGUGCUGCCAGAUCCUGGUAGUGAACGGCGCGGAGCUGGAAGUCCGCGACCGCGACGGGUACGCGGCCGCUGACCUGUCGGACUUCAACGGCCACAGCCACUGCACCCACUGCCUGCGCACGGUGGAGAACCUGAGCAUGGAGCACUGCGUGCUCUCCCGGGAUCCAUCCGUGGAGCUGGAGGCGAAGCAGCCGGAUUCAGGCAUGUCCUCACCCAACACCACGGUGUCGGUCCAGCCUCUGAACUUUGACCUCAGCUCGCCCACCAGCACCCUCUCCAACUACGACUCCUGCUCCUCCAGCCACUCCAGCAUCAAGGGCCAGCACCCUCCACGUGGGCUUUCCAGCACUAGAGCUGCAGACAUACAGAGCUACAUGGACAUGCUGAACCCAGAGCUGGGCCUGCCUUGGGGCACGAUUGGGAAGCCCAUACCCCCACCACCCCCACCCAGCUUCCCCCCGCCACCCCCGCCCCCAGGCACCCAACUGCCCCCACCCCCACCUAGCUACCCAUCUCCCAAGCCUCCUGUGGGACCACAGGCAGCUGACAUCUACAUGCAGACCAAGAACAAACUCCGCCACGUGGAGACAGAGGCCCUCAAGAAGGAGCCGAGCUCCUGCGACGGCCACGACGGGCUACGGAGGCAGGACUCCAGCCGCAAGCCCCGCGCUUUCAGCAAGCAGCCCAGCACGGGGGACUACUACCGGCAGCUGGGCCGCUGCCCCGGCGAGACGCUGGUCGCACGCCCGGGCAUGGCGCACCGCGAGGAGGCGGAACUCCCUGGGAACCACGUGCCUAACGGCUGCGCCGCGGACCCCAAGGCGUCCAGGGAGCAGCAGCUGCCGCCGCCGCCGCCGCCGCCGCCCCUGCCCGAGGCCGCGACUUCGCCGCCGCCGGUCCCGCCUCUGCCCCUCGAGGGCGCUGGCCCUGGCUGCGGGCAGCGCCGCUCCUCCUCGCCCACCGGCAAAGUGAGAGUCCUGAGGCACAGGAAGAGCACCAAGUCUUUCAACGUGAUGUUCCCGAUGGGCGACAACUCGGAGCUACUGGCUGAGAUUAAGGCAGGCAAGAGCCUGAAGCCGACGCCACAGAGCAAGGGGCUGACCACAGUGUUCUCAGGCAGCAGGCAGCCGGCCUUCCAGCCCGAUUGGCCGCUGCCGUCUGUGUCACCUGCACUGUUACCAGUCCGGAGCCCCACACCGCCAGCUGCGGGGUUUCAGCCGCUGCUCAACGGAAGCUUGGUUCCGGUGCCGCCCACUACUCCUGCGCCGGGGGUGCAGCUGGACGUGGAGGCGCUCAUCCCCACGCACGAUGAGCAGGGCCGUCCCAAGCCCGAGUGGAAGCGCCAGGAGGAGGAGGAGGCCCGGCUGGCCAGCAUGCCCGCCUGGAGGUGGGACCUCCUGCGGAAGAAGCUGGAAGAAGAGAGGAAGCAGAAGCGUUGGAGAACCAGUCCCAGCCUUGUGACACUGGGCCCAAUCAGCGUUUAGCCCACCAGGGUCCACCCAGCACCUGCGCUCCCAGCUGUCACAAUGCAAACAACGCUAUCAAGAUCUCCAGGAGAAGCUGCUGCUAUCAGAAGCCACUGUCUUUGCUCAGGCGAACGAGCUGGAGAAAUACAGAGUUAUACUUAGUGAACCCUUGCUGAAGCAGGACAGUAAACAGGUCCAGGUGGACCUCCAGGACCUGGGCUACGAGACUUGUGGCCAAAGCAAGAAUGAGGCUGAACAGGAGGAAACCACCAGUCCCGGACUACAACCAUAGGGCCACCCACCACAUUGAAAACCAGAAGAGCAUUUUGCUGCCGCCGAGCGUGGACGCAGGCGGAUCUCCGAAGAGCUGGGUCGCCAGCCUCUCCCGCGCACGUUGCCUGGCCUCCAGCACCUACUUGGUCCCGCGCGCUCCCUCGUGUCGCCCCUCGGAGCAGCAGCCGCCGCGGUCGCCGCUACCCGGAAAGAAGUCAGAGACGCCGCGAGGUCGCCGCCACCGCCAUGCCCAAGAAUAAAGGUAAAGGAGGUAAAAAUAGACGCAGGGGUAAGAAUGAGAAUGAAUCUGAAAAAAGAGAACUGGUAUUCAAAGAGGAUGGUCAGGAGUAUGCUCAGGUAAUCAAAAUGUUGGGAAAUGGACGGCUAGAAGCAAUGUGUUUCGAUGGUGUAAAGAGGUUAUGUCACAUCAGAGGAAAAUUGAGAAAAAAGGUUUGGAUAAAUACCUCGGACAUUAUUUUGGUUGGUCUCCGAGACUACCAGGAUAACAAAGCUGAUGUAAUUUUAAAAUACAAUGCAGACGAAGCUAGAAGUCUGAAGGCAUACGGCGAGCUUCCAGAGCAUGCUAAAAUCAAUGAAACUGAUACAUUUGGUCCUGGAGAUGAUGAUGAAAUUCAGUUUGAUGACAUUGGAGAUGAUGAUGAAGAUAUUGAUGACAUCUAAAUUGAACUCAACAUUUUACAUUCCAUCUUUUCUGAAGAUUGUCCUACAAUUUGGAUUUUGAUCAUGACAAAGAAGAUUAAAAUUUCAUUAGCAUGAAUGCAAUUUGUUAAAGCAGACUGAUUUGUUUCUAAGAUAUUUUUGGUUUUUUUAAAACUGAUAAUAAUGCUGAAUUAUCUUAAGUGAGAUGUUAAGCCCACUUUGUUCUUUUAAUGUAAUGGAGCUUAUGGGUAGAAGACCAUGUCUACUAAUUACAAAAAAAAAAAAAAAACCAUGCAUUGCUGCUUUUCCUACCACUUCCAGUAAGAAAAUGGGUGUUUUGAAGAAAUCAUUUGCCUUGUCCUCACGGAAUCUGAUUAAGCCCUGGCCUCUUGAUUGUAUAGAGUCAUUGUGUAUAUUCCAGUUACCUAGAUAUUCCCUUGAGAUUUUGAUACAAUUUGAGGGAGGCAGAAGUCUGCAUUUGAAGAAAAAAAAUAAGUCUGUUUGUCAUAUUUAAGUAGCCUGUGGCUAUUUUUAUACUGAUUUUGAUAUCAUGUUCUUUUCAUAGUCGUAUUUUGCCACCGUAAACAUAAAAAAAAAAAAAAAAGAUUUCCAAAAUGCCGUUUUCAGAACCUGG